AGAGGCGCUCAGGGUGGCAGCAGAGCAGACGCCGGGCUGCGCGCUGGGAGCUGCGGUCUCCGGCCAUGGCCCCCGCUCCGCCCCCCGCCGCCUCCUUCUCGCCCUCCGAGGUCCAGCGGCGCCUGGCGGCCGGCGCGUGCUGGGUCCGCCGCGGGGCCCGCCUCUACGACCUCUCCAGCUUCGUGCGGCACCACCCGGGGGGCGAGCAGCUGCUGCGGGCCAGGGCGGGCCAGGACAUCAGCGCCGACCUGGACGGGCCGCCGCACAGGCACUCGGCCAACGCGCGCCGCUGGCUGGAGCAGUACUACGUGGGAGAGCUCCGCGGGGAGCAGCAGGGCUCCAUGGAGAACGAGCCUGUAGCCCUUGAGGAAACUCAGAAGACAGAUCCUGCUAUGGAACCACGGUUCAAAGUGGUGGAUUGGGACAAGGACCUGGUGGACUGGCGAAAGCCUCUCCUGUGGCAGGUGGGCCACUUGGGAGAGAAGUACGAUGAGUGGGUUCACCAGCCGGUGACCAGGCCCAUCCGCCUCUUCCACUCAGACCUCAUUGAGGGCCUCUCUAAGACUGUCUGGUACAGUGUCCCCAUCAUCUGGGUGCCCCUGGUGCUGUAUCUCAGCUGGUCCUACUACCGAACCUUUGCCCAGGGCAACGUCCGACUCUUCACGUCAUUUACAACAGAGUACACGGUGGCAGUGCCCAAGUCCAUGUUCCCCGGGCUCUUCAUGCUGGGGACAUUCCUCUGGAGCCUCAUCGAGUACCUCAUCCACCGCUUCCUGUUCCACAUGAAGCCCCCCAGCGACAGCUAUUACCUCAUCAUGCUGCACUUCGUCAUGCACGGCCAGCACCACAAGAGCAGGAGACUGAGGCCUAGGAGGACUAAGGAACUUGCCCCAGGUCACACUUGGCACAGCCAGGAUGUCGUACCCCAUUCUGGGGAUUCCAGAGUCUGCGCUCUCAAUCACCCUUCCCCUGAGGCCCUUCAAGGACUCCACGACAGUCCCAGAAGCUGGCCCGAGAAGAUAGGUCUGCCCAAAGGAAGCUACCUCCCCUGUACCCCCCGCUGCUUCUCUGUCCCUGCAUUGUGCUGUCCUUGGCCCAUCCCAGGCUGUUCCCCAGCCCGUCUCCACACUCUGUUCUCUGCUGGGCAUAAAUCAGAGAAAAUAUGGCAGAUAUGAUACUUUCGGGACACCAGUUUAGACCCUGAUGUCGCUGAUACUGAACGUGGGUUUCACCUUGGUUUCCCAGCAGCAACUUAAUCCGGUUCAUCUCGAUGAGCCGAUUCGGGGUUUGAUCGGCCGCCUGGGACAGUUCUCAGGUUGGUUGGCUGUGGUCCUCCCGGCUCUCCCCAGAGUUGAUCUGCAUCCUAGGGGGCUUUCCUAGGGGCCAGUAUCAGGGUGGGUGCCCAGUCCUGGGCCAACCUGUCUCUCAGGUAUGCUCUCAGAGGUAGCGCAGCCCAGGCCUGGCCUGUGUCCUCCAGCCUCACCUGGCCUCUGCUCUGCAGAGCUCACUGCAUCUGCUUCUGUGUCCCUUGCCCUGUUUGUGAAGCCUUUUCAGAUCCACUGCCCUGUCCGCUAUCUUUCCCAUCCACAGGGGACACCAGAACCUUCUGGGAACCUGCUCAGGCCAUUCUGGGGCCCCAGGGGCUGUCUCAGGCUCCCUCUUUUGAGACACUUCCACCCCAGUCUGUCCAGUCCCCUGCUGCCACACCAUGAGGACCCGAGGAGACUGUAUGGCCUGUAGCCACGUGGGCUCCAAUCAGGAACGUGUUCUCAGAUCCCCAGACCUAUCCAUCUAAGGAUCCUGAUCCAGCUGUGACCCGGAUCUGGCCCAUACCAGCUCACAAGAGCACCCAUGCACAUCCUUUCCUGUUUCUGUUCCAGUGACGCCACCUCAGCGCUUGAAAGCGCCAGGGCAGUUUUCACACUGCAGGAAUUGGCAAACACUACCAAUCAGGGCUCUCCCUCCCUCCCUUUAUUUCCCCCUCCCUCAUUCCCCAGCUCUCUCCCUUCCUCCUUUUCCUGAGAGCUGGUUUUCCAGCACAUCACUGGUCCUGUUGUUCCUGGUCUGAAGGGAGGGAGGCCCACGCCAGCAUCUCAUUGUGUCACUGUCACCUGCUUUCUCUCUCUCUCCUCCAGCCCAGAGAGGCUGCAGGAUUCUCUUCUCAGACUCCUCACCAAGCCAUAGCUAAGAUCUCACCUCUAUGCCAGGCCCUUGGCUUCUGAAGCUCGAGGGCCACGGUGAAGCGGUGUUCUCUGGUUCACUGUGGCGACACCCCCUUGGAACAAAAAAGGCCUCCUGUUUGGACAUGGGGGUGGGGAGGACACCUCUAGUGACACUUCCGGGUCAUCCCGCCACAGAGGCUGCAUUAACCUCAGUUGCCCUCAGUGCCUUGCUCUCCCAGACAACAUCAGGCCUCAGUCUAGGUGCCCUGUCUCCAGAAUGCCCCUCUAGCCAGGGGCACGGCAUUUAGGGAUGGGAUACCUGUCUAGCACCUGACAAAUUCCAGAGUCACAGUGGCCUCUAUAAGAUGGGCUCUGAGCCGCCAGCACACCCCACCCAUCCUGCCCAUCCUGCCCAUCCCGCCCAUCCCAUGUUCCUUUGCAAUCUGCCAGGUCCCUUCCUGGCUCACAAAUGGGAAGUAAGACAGUCUCUCCAGAUCUUCCAGACGUGGUGGCCCGCCCUCCCCAAAGCCACCAAAGGUGCCAAGCCUACGCAGUGGAAUGUCUGGGCCGCUGUGCCCCUGUCCUCUGCAGGGAGUGGCCAGGGUUUGGCCAGCUGCCGGGGCCCCUGGCUGCCUCCUGAUGCCCAAGCCUCUCCAUCUGCAGGCACCCUUCGACGGCUCCCGCCUGGUCUUCCCCCCUGUGCCAGCCUCCCUGGUGAUCGGCGUCUUCUACUUGUGCAUGCAGCUCAUCCUGCCCGAGGCAGUAGGGGGCACUGUGUUUGCGGGGGGCCUCCUGGGCUACGUCCUCUAUGACAU